GCAGUCGCGCCCGCCGCCGUCGUUGCCCCCGCUGCCGCGGCUGCUGCAGGUGAGGUGAAGUGAGCUCGGGUCCCUUCUGCGCUGCCGCAGGGAGGCCGCCCGGGCCAGGCGAGCCGAACCAAUGCUGGACCUGGAGGUAGUGCCCGAACGCUCUCUGGGGAACGAGCAAUGGGAAUUCACGCUGGGAAUGCCUCUGGCUCAGGCAGUAGCCAUUCUUCAGAAGCACUGUCGCAUCAUCAAAAACGUCCAGGUUCUCUACAGUGAACAGUCUCCUCUAAGCCAUGACCUCAUUCUUAACCUGACUCAGGACGGGAUCAAACUAAUGUUUGAUGCUUUCAAUCAGAGACUUAAGGUGAUCGAAGUAUGUGAUUUGACUAAAGUAAAGUUAAAAUAUUGUGGCGUGCAUUUUAAUUCUCAGGCCAUAGCUCCUACCAUUGAACAGAUUGACCAGUCUUUUGGCGCAACCCAUCCUGGAGGUAAGCCAAGUCCAUCUGAUUCCUCUGGUCAUCAGUGGCAGUUCAUAGCAAUAAACCUGCCCGGUAGUGCCAUCCCACCCCACUUCCUGGAGUCAGGCUCCCAUAGGAUUGUGGGGUUGGUACUUGGGUGUGAAGGAAACAUCCUCCCCCUUGUUUUCAACCUAGUAGGCCAGUUUAGAAACAAGCCACAGGGAAGGUGUUGUCAGUCAUUACUCCCUGCCAGGCUGGUUUAUGUUAGCCAUUUCAGAUGCCAGUCAACCAUGUUAUUUUCUUCUCCCCCACCCCCAACAGUGUACAACUCCGCUGAGCAGCUCUUCCAUCUCAACUUCAGAGGACUGUCUUUCUCUUUUCAGUUAGACUCAUGGACUGAGGCUCCAAAGUAUGAGCCCAAUUUUGCCCAUGGCCUGGCUUCUCUCCAGAUACCCCAUGGAGCAACUGUAAAACGAAUGUACAUCUACAGUGGCAACAGCCUGCAGGAUACCAAGGCUCCCAUGAUGCCUCUGAGCUGUUUCCUGGGCAAUGUCUAUGCUGAGAGUGUAGAUGUUCUUCGAGAUGGAACUGGACCUGCAGGUUUACGACUUCGCCUACUUGCUGCAGGUUGUGGACCUGGCCUAUUAGCAGAUGCCAAGAUGCGGGUAUUUGAACGUUCAGUGUAUUUUGGUGAUUCCUGCCAAGAUGUUCUUAGCAUGCUUGGCUCUCCACACAAAGUCUUCUAUAAAUCAGAAGACAAGAUGAAAAUUCAUUCUCCUUCCCCUCAUAAACAAGUUCCAUCGAAGUGUAAUGACUACUUUUUUAACUACUUCACUCUUGGAGUGGACAUCCUCUUUGAUGCGAAUACACACAAAGUGAAGAAGUUUGUUCUACACACCAAUUACCCUGGGCAUUAUAAUUUCAACAUUUAUCAUCGCUGUGAGUUCAAGAUCCCACUAGCCAUAAAGAAAGAAAACGCAGAUGGUCAGACAGAAACAUGCACGACCUACAGCAAGUGGGACAACAUCCAGGAGCUCCUGGGCCACCCUGUGGAGAAGCCUGUUGUCCUGCACAGGUCUUCCUCCCCAAACAACACCAACCCAUUUGGUUCCACAUUCUGCUUUGGUCUUCAGCGAAUGAUCUUUGAGGUCAUGCAGAACAACCACAUUGCCUCGGUGACCCUGUAUGGCCCCCCCAGGCCUGGUAGCCACCUGAGAACAGCGGAACUCCCCUAGGGACACCACCACCCAUGCCCCUCUGUCCCGUGGAACUGUGCAUCACAUCCUGCUCAGUGGGCCUCUGUACCACCCUGUGGGUUUUCUUGGACACCUGGCCAGUGCUGAAGGGCUGUUGUGAUGUUCUGAGGUUGGGCUCAGGCUGGGUGCUCUGCCAUGGGCUGAGUGGCCCAGAUAUUCUUCUGUCCAUCUUUGGCCUGCUGGUGCCAGCAGGGGACACAGACUGCAAAGAGAAGCACAAAGUUUGAGCCUUGAUUCCUGGACCCAGGAGCUCUCAACUAACAAGGAGGCAGGAGAGGUCAACCCUUGUCCCAUGCACAUUGGGAAGACUUGGGGCUCUUUCUGUGACUGAGGACACAGGCACCCAGGAUAAGGACAAGGUCCUGCCUUUGGCUCCACAUUGCCACAUGACCCUUAAGGCAAGCAGGUAGCGUGUCCAUAGUACUUGGUUGCGACAUUUGCACUACAUCCACUUUAGUUACUUGAUGAGCUGGCUGUGGCCAGGGUGGCCCACCUGCCCUUCCCUGUUCCUUUCUUGCACGCGCUCCCUGCCUGGGCACACCAAACUGGUUGAAACACAGCUUUCUACCAUCCAGGUACAUGCCCAGGCCUGGUUCUCACCCCUGUUGGAGUCAGCUUUCAAGAUUGCCUGUGCCCCUGCUCUGCCCCAUCCUGGCUGGCAGGGCUGCAUGUUUCCAUCCUGUUUGCCUCUUUUAUUUAAUGCCAAAGUUUUAGCCAAAGACAUCUUCCUACUUUUGUUGUGUUUCAGCAUUCUGUUCUGCACUGUGGGCUGGCUCUCUGCCCCAACCCUGGGCACUGGCCCCUGGCUGGGCCAUUUCAUGGCUCAAAGCCUCUGGGGGCUCAAGGAAGGCUGGGCUGCUCAGUCCCUUCAUGGGUCUUGCUAAUGGAAAGUAGCAUAUAUGUGCUUUAAAAAUAUUAAUCCUUUUGAAAAGAACUGAGAAGAAAAAUGUAUAAUUUUAUCCCAUUUUUAAUAUUUUGGUCUAGCAACUUGUGAUACAUAGAUGACAAUUUUGUGAGUUUUUCAAAUGUGUGUACAGAUUUUUGUAAAUAUGACUCUUUUGUAAUUAACUCAUGUACAGCCUCAUCCUGUAUAGUUUAAUGAUGAAUGUGCAGGGGACCUGUCUCAGGCUCCUAUAUGGUUCCUGGGCCUUAUAGCCAGGUUUGUGUGGCGCUCCCGACUUUUGUGACUGACUGGUGUCUUCCCAUUUGGACUGUGGCCUGGCCAGAGCCCCUUGCAUAUCCCCACUGUCAGGGGCAGCCAGGACUGUUCCCAUCCUCCUGGAAUGGGGGAACCUUCCUUAUCCCCUGCCCACAUCCCCUCUCCAAUAAAGCACCUGUGCCCUCAGCAAUGGCCUGCCAUGUGCUGUUGCUGGGAUGUUUGUAUUAAGGUAA